GUAAACUUGCCUCGGUCCCGGUGGGGGCAGCCGCGGCGGUGGGGUUGGCAGGGUGUGCUGGGGCCUGGAGGAGGCGCCGCGCGGCCAGGGAGCCAGCGGGAGGCCGCGCCUGGCAGGUUUCUGAAACAGAUCGUGAGCUUCAUCAAGAGAAUUCAACUGGAAAACCAAGACUGGUAGACUCUCUUUUUCUUCAGACAAUAGGCAGGAGCCAGGCAGAGUCCAGGGAUUCUUGGAACACCUAUCUUUUCUUCGGAGGACACUAAGUUCUAUUUGAAGACAAAGUUCAAUAUGGCAACAGGACUGAUGGGACACGAAGGAGUCGCUACCGUGAUUUGGUGACAGUUCUUCAAAACGACAGUGUCUCAAGGAAAGGUGGACCUAGGAACUCCUGAACUUUUGGGUUGCCUUAAGUGAGAAAUCAGCAUGGCUCAGGCAAGUCUCCUGGCUUGUGAAGGCCUAGCAGGUGUGAGUUUGGUUCCCACUGCAGCCAGCAAGAAGAUGAUGCUGAGCCAGAUUGCCAGCAAGCAGGCCGAGAAUGGCGAGCGGGCAGGUAGCCCUGAUGUGCUGAGGUGCUCGAGUCAGGGUCACCGAAAAGACAGUGAUAAGUCCCGGAGCCGCAAAGAUGAUGACAGCUUGUCUGAGGCCUCUCAUUCAAAAAAGACUGUUAAAAAGGUGGUGGUAGUGGAACAAAAUGGUUCUUUUCAAGUAAAGAUUCCCAAAAAUUUUGUUUGUGAACACUGCUUUGGAGCCUUUCGGAGCAGUUACCACCUAAAGAGGCACAUCCUUAUUCACACUGGUGAGAAGCCAUUUGAAUGCGAUAUAUGUGAUAUGCGUUUCAUCCAGAAGUACCACCUGGAACGCCACAAGCGUGUGCACAGUGGUGAAAAGCCUUACCAGUGUGAACGGUGUCAUCAGUGUUUUUCUCGGACAGAUCGAUUACUCAGACACAAACGGAUGUGCCAAGGGUGCCAGUCCAAGACUUCCGACGGGCAGUUUUCUCUAUAGGCGCAAGGGGCCCCGGGUGGUGGGAGUGAUCAGAAGAACCUGCCGAAGAGCACACCCCCUCUGGUCUGAUGGUCCCACCACCGCCCCAUGUGAACCUGUCCCACUCCUGGAGGAGUGGACCCAGGAGACCAGAAGAGUGCAUCAGGGGACAGUGGCCCCAGAACCUCAGCUCUGUAAAUAAUCUGAGACUAUGAGUAUCUCGGGGAAGUUCUUACAGCAUUCCUGGGUAGGGGAGCUAGUCCCUGGACCCUUGGCUGAGGUCAUAGGUGGGGACUCAAGGUACAGGACCAAGACUGAAGUGUGGCUCCCACAACCUUGGACUCCAGCUGGCAGCUGAAAUGGAAAAGAUUGGGGAAGGGGAUUUGUUUGUUCUGUUCUUGUUUUUGUUUAUCCAAAAGCAACUUCAGCGGGUAAACUGUGGAUACAGGUAAUCCAGAGGCAUAAGAGUCCUGGUCCAAAGUAGGGACUAUAGCUGGUCCAGCUCUCCCCAAAAAUUGGGUUUUUAGUUGCAGUAGCUCCUCAGUGUUUCACAAUCCUGCACUUCGCCUCCUUUUUGAGGAAGAAUAAGGUCAGGAAUGGCAGCUGAGCUUACUUUGGCUUCCUUAUACACUGUAGGGACAAAAGGAAAAACGGGGUGGAGCAGACAAGGGCUGGAUCCAAAAAGUGGAUGGCACCUCUUCCUUCCUCAAGGGAAAAGGAAGAGUUGUGCCAGUGGGUGUUGUCAUGGCCCAUGUCACAUUGGCACCUGAUGGCAUCAGCUCAAAUGCCUUUAGGAGGAAACUUGGGUGAGAGUGGCCCAUGAAGCCCUUUUCUUCUUUUUUUGGGGAGUCGGUCUUGGAGAUGGUAUGUGGCUACCUCGCUGCCAUUGACUCCUAAAGUGAGACAGAUGUGUUGAGCAAGGAGUCAUGGAAGUCAAAGUGGGUUCUCUCUCCUUGUGCCCUCUUAGGAACAACCCAAGACUGGUCCCAAGUUGGCUAACAGCUGCUCAAGAAACAAAGGAAUCUGGGGUCUUCUGACAUGCCUGUUGAGCAGUAGGAGCUGUUCUCCCUCCCCAAGUCCUAUCACUGUAUUCAGGUAGAGGAGGUAGGGAGGGGUCUGUCCUUUGGUCCCAAAAAACAAGAUCUCGGCUUGCUUCCUGAUGGCCAUCCCUACCCAACAGAGUGUGGGGGAUGGGGGUGGGGGUGCUGCAGAGAAAAGACUAAAGAAGAAACCUAAUGUAGGUUCCAUUCUUAACCAUAUUCUUUGCUCCUCUCUGCUCCAAUACCACCACCUUGUCCACUCCCAAAAAAGUAAUCGGGUGUGUGUGUGUGUGUGAGAGAGAGUGUGUGUGAGAUAUGAAUGCAUGUAUUUGUAUGCUUGCAGGAGAUGGCAUAUUAUUGAGCCAAACCCUUCUCUGGCCCUCACCUUCAGGGAGGAUGAGUGGAAAAUAGCCUCCUCUUGCCCAAACAUGAAGGGUGCUUGAGGUCUCAGCAGGAGCUGAAGAACACAAUUUGGGGAACAGAAGGGCUUUUGUUUUGGAGGGUUUUUUUUUUUAAGAUGAAUUCAACAGCCUGGUGGUUAGGAUGUUUCUAACCCAAGCCAGGGCUUGUGAACAUGAAUUUUCUAAGGUGAAAUAAACCUUUUCUUUCUGCUAAAGAAAGAAUCCUUAUGGGAAGUUUUGGGGUUUGGUUGACCCCCACUGUAACCUGACCUGACCUGUGGCGGGUACGGGAACUGUCUUAGUAAUCAUGGAGACUGGCUGAACCUGAGUGCCAAGCUGUCAGUAGGGUCUGAGAUGGGAAACUCCUGAAAGUAUGAUUUCAUUUCCCAGAAAAUGUAAAGAAUGGAUACCAGCAAUGAUUCCUGGCUGUUACCUAUUCUGGAGGGGUGGGGUUGGGGAGGGGGUUGUCCAUACCUCUGUGGUAUGAGUAUUUCAGGGAAAAAGAAAGCAGGCAUGGCACCCAUUCGAUUUUCCCUGACAGCAUCUGAGAUCCUUUUGGGGAGACGCUGAGGAGUGUUUGCUGCCAUGUACUCUUACAGCUCUAUGCUGACACUCCCAUUUGAUGUGGUCCAGAACUUAGACCUCAGUCCUUGGAUCAGCCCUGUGGUCCCUGCAAGCAGGGGCAUCUUUCUGCAUGUGAGCCAGCCCCCUUCCUGUUCAAGGGUUCUGCUGGAUCUGGGCUUUUCCUGUCCUUCACUUCUGGGAUGAUUCACCCCACAUCUUCCAGUACCCUGUAAACCAUUUUAAAAUAUUUAGAAAACUAUCCUCCCAAAAAUGCUUUUGAAAAUGAGAGCCCUCUGUCCCUGCCACUUACAGCUAGUCUCUUUGGGAUAGGGGUGUAUGUGGAGAGAUUCAUGUAAGUCUCACAUGAGUGACCUGUGCCCCUAUGUGUACUAAUGUGUGUACUGGGUCAGAAGGUGCCCUGGGUUCCCACAGACCUUGGUUUCCUGCCUGGGUGGGUGGGAGGGAGGGAACUUCAGAGAGUAUGUGCGAACAGCCAUAGCAGAGCCACCCCUGCCAAGGACCCAGUGAGGGAAACUCAGGAGCAGGUGGUUGGUUCAGUUCCCGCGCUGAUGUCUGGGGCAGUGCAUGUGUGAGAAGAGAGGCGCAAAGCAGUGAAAGGAGUGAUUUGGCAUCCAGAGGGCCCGGGAGCCCCACGGAUACCCCAGGGAAGCCACUGACUCACACCGCUGCAGAGGCUCCUGGGCCCAAUGCCCGACCCCUGCUGGCCAGCAUGGGGCCUAGCACUGGAAGAUGCCUCAGGUGUGUUUGGAGUGGGGGAAACGGAAGUAGGGCACGCUCUCAGAGACCAGGAUAGAGAGUCAGGGAACCUGGGAAAGAGUAGUGCCAGUUCCGGGUAGGCUGCUGCACCAGGCCCUACCAGCUCAGGCUAUAAACAGUCUGCUUUGCCCCAAGUCUUUUCCGUCCACCCCCAACAGCCUUGUCAUCACUUAGCUACUGAUCACGCCCAUGGCUUGACAUUGGAGGGUUACAUUAGUGGAGUCCGCCACAGCUUCGAACCCUCUCCCCAGAUGCCCUUUGCCUCUGCUGUGGCCCUGGGGUUUUAUCAACUGUCCCCUUCCUAUCCUCCUCUCCACCCUGUUUUUUGUUUUUUUUUUUUUUAAAUAAUAUUUUGCUAUGGGGGAGGGGAAUAUCAAAUGGACAAGAUCACUUUUAAAUGGUAGUUUUUAUAAGAUGUUAUAAACUUGUAUCUUUUUACCAUUAAAGUGCAGUGUAUGUUCCUUCGUGAUAUAUUUAGGAUAUUUAAAUAAAAGGAAAAUGGGGCUUUUCUACAUACUAUCUCCUCUUUGGGGAAGCUUUUUCAUACUGGUUUUAGUUGUUUUCCUUUUUUCUCCCUACAUAAUCACCCCACAACUUCCAGCACCCUAUAAGCCAUUUUAAAACCCCUUCUCCACAGAGGAACAAGCAAGUAGGAGCAAAAACAGGGCAUCAGUUCUGAGCAAGACGAAAAAGCACACGCAGCAGGACGGAAGGAGGCUAGACACCAACAGAUGCAGUGUCUCUGACCUGGGACCCCCCUGCAUCCGCAGCACUUGAGAAUUCAUAGGCCCUUUCCAGACCUGGCUUCCUGGGUCCCAGGGUGCACCCCGGGAGUUUCCUGCACAUUCGCGCUUGGGCACCUCUCCCUGCCCUCAGGUGGCAAGAGGAGGAUGGACAAGAGCUUUCCCGAGGCCCAGGCUAUAAACAGUCUGCUUUGGCCUUGAUGAGGUAAAGCAAAGUGACAGCUGUGGUCUGAGGUAAGACUUUAUUGUAUACUUGGGUGGGGUAGCCCAGAUGGAUGCAAGGUUGCAGGCAUGGGAAGCAGCCCUCUUGGGUGUCACUCUGAAAAUGAAGUAGGGUGGUGGCCGCACCUCGCCAGUGAAUUAGUCCCCUACCAAGGUCUUACAGACCCACCCUUCCUCUCACCCUCCAGUUCCCACUGUCCUCCAAGGAGAAGAGCCUUGGGUAAGUGUCCCUCCCUCCUUCAGAGAGUGGGACUGUCUGCCUCUUGAAAGCGAGGAUUGAUGGUGGUCGUGAUGGCACUUUUGUAGAGAGGAUUACUGUCCUGGAGAAAGAUGUUGCAGAUUAUAAGCAAAAAUCCCAGGAUUCCUCGUCCCCUUUCUAGACCUAAGAGGCCAGCCUUGAGCCGAAUCCUAGGAGCUGAUGGAAGUUAGCAGAGGGGUUGGUUACAUGUGCCAGGGGCUGGGGGAACCCAGUGGGAGGAAUCAGGGCUGGUCUUGUGGUGGGGGAACAGCUAAAAAGGGGCCUAACCAGGAAGUCUCCUCACCUGCUUCCAGUUGAGUUGUUGCUGCUCCUUCUCAAAGCGACUGUAUUCCCGGCGGUCAUAGAUUUCCACCGAGAGCCGGUAAGCCAGGACCAGCCCCAGCCCCACUGCCACGAUGCCCCCUACGCAGCCCAGCACAAUGGCCUGCGUGUGGUCUGCUCCCUCUGUGAACAAGAAACCAGACACACUUGUGGGAGCUGGAGCAUAGGGACAGAUCAUCAGUUGCUCACAGUGUGUCCAGCCUGUCCAACCCUGUCUGUCACUGAAAGCAAAGGGAACCCAGGGAGGUCCAAGGUUAUCCUCACCGCCCAGGGCCUUAGCCUCGUCCACUUGCUCAAUUGCCUCUGCCUUUGUCCUGGAUUCACAGUUCUGCUUCAGCCCCCAGCCUGUUUCCCAUUAUCUUCACUCUGCAUCCCCAGAGUUGAGACCCUGCCCAUCAAACUUCCAGGGUUUGUGGCAUCCCUGCCCACUUACUUUCUUGGGGUCUCACUCUGAGCACGACCGUGCCUCUGGCGUCAUCCUCCACCAAGAAGAAGAACAGCUGGUUGUCCAGGGUCCGCUCUUUGCACCAGCCAUCAUCCAAGAUAGGGGCCAAGGCCAGGGUCACAUUGGUAUGGGCACAAGCUGUACUGCAGUUGGUGGCCAGUGGGCCAGUCCUGAAGGCCCCACACUCUGCACAGUCCCUGUGUAGUAGAUGCCAAUAGGUUACCAGCUGGGCAGUUGUCACCCAAUGCCCCUUGCCCAACUACAAGCAGGACGGAGAGUAGGCAGAUGGGAGUAGCUCAACAAGCCCCACUGUGCCCCUGCUCCCAAGAUGCAAGACCUGAGGCCUCACCGGUGUCUCUCGCAUGGUGUCUUGCAGCCUGGGCAUUGGUCGCAUAGAGCACCAUAGUAGCCGUCCAAGCACUGGCAGCGGUUGCAUUUGCAGCGUCCAUGCCCACUGCAGAGCCCUCCCUCGGGACUGAUGCAACUGUCCAUGUCCCCACUGCAUUCGCAUGCUCUGCCCGUGCGGUUGGCAUGACAGUGACAUACUCCACAUUGGCAGCGACCAAAGCCUGGGGUAGAGCCAUGCAGAGGGUGACAACCAUACUCCACACACACAGUUGGCCAUCAUGUGGCACGACAAGCCCACGCAUCCAAUCUUUUUGAAGUAUGCCAACCACACCCUCUAACCCAUACACCGGAAUCUUUUGAUAUUUGCCUUCCAUGCCAGGAGAUUCCCAGAGCCUAAGUGCCUUGGGAAGGCCUCUCAGACCCCGCCCUUCUCCCCAAGGCUCCAGGUACCUCCGCAGAGGAUGCCCUCAUGUCGCUCACAGCUGGCAUCGUCACACUCGCACAGAUGCCCAGAGCUCUGUCCACUGCAGCUGCAGCGUCCACAUUGACAGUGACCCUUUCCACUGCACAGGGGCCCUGUGCCAUUGGGAGCCCGGCACCCAGAUUCCAGGUCUGGGGAGGACAGCUCUGCCACAGAGCACUCACAGAGCCGACCUAGGCGGCCAGGGGCACAGCUGGAAGGGGAAGGCAAAGGAGAGAAGUAGGUCAGAGGGUUUGAUCACCCCUGACUUGUCUCUCCCAGGAACCUCUAAACCCAAGUUCUCAAAAGAGUUGGAGACAGACAAACAGCUGAAAGGAUGUUAAGUAUAGUGAAACACUGAGGGGUGAGAGAGUGGAGGGAGCCCCAGUCAGGGGGAGGGCCUGGACAUACAUGGGAAGCUUCAAGGGAUGAAACUGAGUGGGGAGUCGGGAUGUCGAGGAGACUCCUGUGGGGGGGAUGGAAAGCAGCGGAGGAAUACGGGCCAGGGUUGGUUGGUUGUUGGGAGCCAGGUGGUUGAAGGGAAGAGGAGGCCCUCACCUGCAUACACCACAUUGUAGGUGUCCCUGGCCAUCACUGCAGUGGGGAGCCUGGGGCUGGGUGUCACUGCAAUUACAGUCACACAGCGUGUGCAACUCCACAAUCAGCUCCUCUGAGAAGCCAAGGGCCCGGAGCCUCAGGAGAUGGGGCUCUGGGAGGCAGUGGGUGGCUUGGAGAGAAACCCAGAAAGUCACCUGAGAAGAGGCAGGAAUCAGGCCAUGGUUAUACACAUGCACACACACAUACCCCAAACUCACCAAUCAUCCAGAACCUCACCCCUUAGUAAAUGAAGGGAUGGGGUCAUGUUAACACCCAACUCCUAGAAACAUGCCUGAGGAAGCCACUCAGACUGCUCCAGGAAGGAUGGAUGGAGGACUACCUCAGGCUCUCAUGUCACUCCCUGUACCUGCCACCCAUCUUUUCCUGCCUGCUUAAUUUCCCACUCCCACCUCCCCCUGCCCGCCUUCUGCCUGUGCUUGCUGGCUCUCACCGUCUGGUUGAUUCGGACGUGGUUGCACUGUCCUCGAUCCUCAGCCUUACCCUCCCUCUUCUCAGGACCCUCACACUGGGAUUCGUAAGAAAUGUGGACCCCAGGAGGGAGUGAAGAGUGUUCAAGGGUCACGGUGGAAGACAGGCUCUAUGGGAAGAGAGCGAGUGGAUAACCACGUGAAGGCAGAAAAGGACUCCAACCCCACCUUAUGUCCUCUCCAGGUGUUCCCAAUUCUGCCAGCACCCUGCCCUCUGCCACCUGGGGCUCCUUCCAUUCUGCCCAGUCGAGGCAUUUCUGGAGGGAGGACCCGUGAGAACCUUGCAUAGAACAUACAGGAUCCAGAGGCCUCUAAUACAGCAUUUCAGUGCAGCUGCCAGCAAGGGCCACUGAGGGUCACAGGCUGGCCAGGUGCUGUAAAUGUACAGAGACCAUGUUUGUGAAGCCCCACAUCAGGACACAUAACCUGGGUGCAUGCCAGGUCUAAAGGGCAGAUUCAUUACAGAGUUUAUCUUGGGAAAUUUGAUACUGUCUCAGAUUUUCUUGCCAUAGGUUUAGGAGAUGCUCCCUGUUAUCAAGAAGCCUACAGCCUAGUUGCAGAGGUAAGACCUAAACCACUAAGAAUUUUUAUGGUUCCUUCUACCUGUAAAAUUCUAUGGUUCUUGUGAAGAAUAGCUCUGAAUUAUUUAUAAACUUAGUGAAAGCAGGCUCCAGAUCUCACAUUGUUUAUGUACAGACUGACUGGGGACAAAUGCCAGCCCUUCUGUUUGUUAUCUUUGUGACCUUGGACAAGUCACUUAGCCUCCUUGUGUGGGUUUCCUCAUCUGUAAAAUAGGGAUGGUAACAGUUAUGAAGCAAGGCUUUUGGCAGGGUUAAAUGAAGUAGCAAACAGUAUGUACACCUAGGAUGGUGGGCGCAUGAAAUAAAAGCUCAGUGAUUGAAACUUUC